AGGCGGGCCAUGGCGGAUGUCCCCGGGGCACAGCGAGCGGUUCCUGGUGACGGCCCAGAGCCCCGGGACCCCCUGGACUGUUGGGCCUGCGCUGUUCUUGUAACAGCCCAGAAUCUGCUGGUGGCUGCCUUCAAUCUUCUCCUGCUGGUGCUGGUGCUAGGGACCAUCUUGCUACCCGCUGUCACCAUGCUGGGCUUCGGCUUCCUCUGCCACUCUCAGUAUCGCCUGGUCGGCUUGGGCCUGACGCCUCUUCUCCCACAGUUCCUGCGCUCCCAGGCACCCCCUUGCACCGCGCACCUGCGGGACCCCGGUUUCACGGCCCUACUGGUCACCGGAUUCCUGCUCCUCGUGCCGCUGCUCGUGCUUGCUCUGGCCAGCUACCGCCGCCUCUGCCUGCGCCUCCGCCUAGCCGAUUGCCUCGUGCCCUACAGCCGAGCCCUUUAUCGGCGUCGGCGCGCCCCGCAGCCGCGGCAAAUCCGGGCCUCACCAGGGUCCCAGGCCGUUCCCACAUCAGGAAAGGUCUGGGUCUAAUGACCCUCGAGUCAAGAACAACCCUGACGGCUGCCCUCCCUCUUAUUCGGCCCAAGGACUUGAAGCCCGGCAUCUUCCGACCUGCCCUGCCCCCACCCCUGCCUGAGCGGAGUCCUAGCAUCCCCUUGGGAGCAGCAGCGUCAGUGGACCCAGUGCUGAGAAAAGCCCCCACAUCCCGGAAAACCCACUUUCCUUUCACGACCCACAUCUCAAUCCUGAACAUCUAGGCUGGAACCUGCACACCUCCCCCUCAGCUCCGUCGUGAAUGGGACAACAAUCUCGUGCCCUCGUUUUAUGGUGCAGCUUCUCUAGUAUUUCUGGGGCUGGGGGGCGGGGCUGGAGGGGAAGGAGUGUCCACGCAUCAAUAAAGAUUUAACGAACUGAA